GCCGCCAUCUUGGGGCUGCUGGGACUCGCGUCGGUUGGCGACUCCCGGACGUAGGUAGUUUGUUGGGCCGGGUUCUGAGGCCUUGCUUCUCUUUACUUUUCCACUCUAGGCCACGAUGCCGCAGUACCAGACCUGGGAGGAGUUCAGCCGCGCUGCCGAGAAGCUUUACCUCGCUGACCCUAUGAAGGCACGUGUGGUUCUCAAAUAUAGGCAUUCUGAUGGGAACUUGUGUGUUAAAGUAACAGAUGAUUUAGUUAGACAGUGUCUUGCUCUAUUGCUCAGGCUGCAGUGCAGUGGCAUGAUCAUAGCUCACUGCAUCCUCGACCUCCUGGGCUCAAGCGGUCCUCUUGCUUCAGCCUCCUGAAUAGCAGAGACUACAGUGUUUGGUGUAUAAAACAGACCAAGCUCAAGAUGUAAAGAAGAUUGAGAAAUUCCACAGUCAACUAAUGCGACUUAUGGUAGCCAAGGAAGCCCGCAAUGUUACCAUGGAAACUGAGUGAAUGGUUUGAAAUGAAGACUUUGUCGUGUACUUAGGAAGUAAAUAUCUUUUGAAUUAGAGAAAGUGUUGGGACAGAAAGUACUUUAUGUAACUAAGUGGGCUGUUCAGAAGCUUAGAGGUCAUUUUUUGUAAUUUUCUUUUUAAUUACUUUAGAGAGCUAGGGAUGCAAAUGUUUUCAGUUAGAAAGCCUUUAUUUACUUUUGGAAAUUGAACAAGAAAUGCAUCUGUCUUAGAAACUGGAGAUUAUUUGAUGUUAGGUAAAACAUGUAAUUGUUUCUCUGGCAAAUUUGUAUCAGUAAUUUGAAAAUGAGAUAUUAGGAAAAACCAAUUCUUCUUAAAUUUAGUUCAUCUUUCUUUAAAAGAACAUUAAAUGUAACCAUUUUGUCAGAUCCAUGUAUUUUGGAGCAUAAAAUGUAUGCUGUUGUGACCAAUAAAUAUAAAAUAUGGUAAUUGGAAUUAACUCCACACCAUAGUAUGCAUUGUUAUACAUACUGUGUACCUAAUUAUGUAUAGCAGUGUAGUCUCAAUUAUAUCUGAAAGUAAUUGUGACUAACAAGUAUGCUUUGCCUUAUUUCCACAUUUAAACUACCUGUUAAUAUAAGGGAUUUGUAGUAUCAGCUUGUUGAGCAAUGACUUUGAAUCUAGUUUUCAGUGAUCAGAAGCAGCAGUUAUUUGAGUGUAUGAAUGGAAUGAUGAUCACUGUGCUAUAAUGUACUGAAACCACCAUAUUACAGAAAUAUUUACUACAUAUUUUCCAUCUGUAGUUUCUCAGAAGGGCUAUGGAUUAGUUUGAACUGUCAAAUCCUUGCAUACUUCUGUGACACCCCUGCCCAUUUUCUGUCUUUAAUUAACCAAGGUGUUAGGUGUGACUGUCACAACUGUUAUGUUUUCCAGUAAACUAGAAGUACGAUAUUUGAUAAUUAUAUUUGUAUUUCACCACCUAAAUGUAAUGUUGAUUCCUCAAGAAUGAAAUGAAGGCACUACAUUGAAAUAUGUUUUGUAUAAAUUUGUCAUGUUGAACAGCAUUUUAGCAUGGUAAGUUCCCUUAGCUAUAUGAAUUUUGGCAUGUUUCAGAGAGAUCAGUAAAUAAAAUAUUAGAUAAAAUA